AUAGGCAUGAGCCCCUGGCCCUGGCCCCAUUUCUCUUUUUAAAAAUUUUCUAUUUGGAAAUAAUUUCAAAUUUUCAGAUACGUUUCAAGAAUAAGAAUAGGACAAAGAAUACCCAUGUACUCUUUACUCAGAUUAAUAUUAAAAGAUUAACAUUUCUAGGUCCGGGUGCAGUGGCUCACACCUGUAAUCCCAGCACUUUGGGAGGCCAAGGUGGGUGGAUCAUGAGGUCAGGAGUUUGAGACCAGCCUGGCCAACAUGGUGAAACCCUGUCUCUACUAAAGAUACAAAAAUUAGCCAGCCAUGCUGGCACAUGCCUGUAAUCCCAGCUACUCGGGAGCCUGAGACAGAAAAAUUGCUUGAACCCAGGAGGCAGAGGUUGCAGUGAGCCGAGAUUGCACCACUGCAUUCCAACCUGCAUGACAGAGCAAGACUCUGUCUAUGGAAAAAUAAAUAAAUAAAAAUAACAUUUCUUUUAAUUAUAAAAGCAGCAUUUUCUCUUAGCAAAAUUUCAGAAACAUGUAAUGUACAAAAUGGCAGUCUCCUCCUUCCAGCUCCCUUGGGGUUGCCAUUUUUGUGAGUUUGGAGUGCAUUCUUCCAUAUCUCUUUCUAAGCUCUGUGCCUGGGAGGGAGCCCUGUGGGUUGGGAGCUCUGGGGUGCGAAUGGUAUCUGAGGACUCAUUUCCACAUAGAGUUGGACACCAUGAUUGCUCAAGGACAGGCAGUGAAGUGGGAAAACAAAAUGCUGCAGCUGGUGCCCAGGGCAGGGCAGCUCCUUGGUUAGCUUAAUGGAAACAUUCAACGAGAAGGCUGAGCAGCUGGUGGAGAUUCUAGAAGCCAAGGCAGAUGGGCAGACCCCAGUGUCCAUGCAGGACAUGCUGACCUACACCGCCAUGGACAUCCUGGCCAAGGCAGCUUUUGGGAUGGAGACCAGUAUGCUGCUGGGUGCCCAGAAGCCUCUGUCCCAGGCAGUGAAACUUAUGUUGGAGGGAAUCACUGCGUCCCGCAACACUCUGGCAAAGUUCCUGCCAGGGAAGAGGAAGCAGCUCCGGGAGGUCCGGGAGAGCAUUCGCUUCCUGCGCCAGGUGGGCAGGGACUGGGUCCAGCGCCGCCGGGAAGCCCUGAAGAGGGGCGAGGAGGUUCCUGCCGACAUCCUCACACAGAUUCUGAAAGCUGAAGAGGGAGCCCAGGACGACGAGGGUCUGCUGGACAACUUCGUCACCUUCUUCAUUGCUGGUCACGAGACCUCUGCCAACCACUUGGCGUUCACAGUGAUGGAGCUGUCUCGCCAGCCAGAGAUCGUGGCAAGGCUGCAGGCCGAGGUGGAUGAGGUCAUUGGUUCUAAGAGGUACCUGGAUUUCGAGGACCUGGGGAGACUGCAGUACCUGUCCCAGGUCCUCAAAGAGUCGCUGAGGCUGUACCCACCAGCAUGGGGCACCUUUCGCCUGCUGGAAGAGGAGACCUUGAUUGAUGGGGUCAGAGUCCCCGGCAACACCCCGCUCUUGUUCAGCACCUAUGUCAUGGGGCGGAUGGACACAUACUUUGAGGACCCGCUGACUUUCAACCCCGAUCGCUUCGGCCCUGGAGCACCCAAGCCACGGUUCACCUACUUCCCCUUCUCCCUGGGCCACCGCUCCUGCAUCGGGCAGCAGUUUGCUCAGAUGGAGGUGAAGGUGGUCAUGGCAAAGCUGCUGCAGAGGCUGGAGUUCCGGCUGGUGCCCGGGCAGCGCUUCGGGCUGCAGGAGCAGGCCACACUCAAGCCACUGGACCCCGUGCUGUGCACCCUGCGGCCCCGCGGCUGGCAGCCCGCACCCCCACCACCCCCCUGCUGAGGGGGCCUCCAGGCAGGACGAGACUCCUCGGGCAAGGGCCGUGCCCGCCCACCUCUGCUGCCCACGGCCACCCACCCUUCUCCCCUGCCCCGUCCCCUGGGCCACCCUUCACGCUGGCUUCCAGCGGGCCCUCUGCCGACCGCCUGCUUCACACCCCUCAGCGCUCCCUGUCGCCUGCGGACUCCAUGGCCCUUCCUGGACUGGCCCUUGCCCAACUCCCAGCCACCACCACUGUCCCUACCACUGAGCCCUUGCACAGGCCACUUGCUCAGACGAGACACCCUAACUCUUGCUCACUCCCUAAAGCCCUCUUCAGGGGUCACCUCCUCCAAGAAGCCCUCCUUGCCACCCCCCGCCGGCAGGGGCCCCUCCUCUGUGCUCCCUCGGUCACCUGUGCUACCUCUAACACCACACUGACCACACUGUAUCGUGAGUGUCCGUUGACGUGACCAAUUGCCCUGCCAGGCUGUCAGCGCCUCAAGGGUAGGGUCUGCGUGUGAUUUGUCUCUGAGCCCCCUGUGCCCACCCAGGGCCCGGCACAGAGUCGAUGCUCAAUAAAUGUGUGUUGACUGCA